GGGAGUGGCGUGCUGGGCGUGCGCGGCUGCGGUACGGCGUGUUGGUCCCAGCGGUUCAGCUGAGGUAGGGACGUGCUGUAGGCCGGAAUGUUACCGGCUGUUGGAUCUGCGGAUGAGGAGGAGGAUCCUGCGGAGGAGGAUUGUCCUGAAUUGGUUCCCAUUGAGACGACGCAAAGCGAGGAGGAGGAAAAGUCUGGCCUCGGCGCCAAGAUCCCAGUCACAAUUAUCACCGGGUAUUUAGGUGCUGGGAAGACAACACUUCUGAACUAUAUUUUGACAGAGCAACAUAGUAAAAGAGUAGCGGUCAUUUUAAAUGAAUUUGGGGAAGGAAGUGCGCUGGAGAAAUCCUUAGCUGUCAGCCAAGGUGGAGAGCUCUAUGAAGAGUGGCUGGAACUUAGAAACGGUUGCCUCUGCUGUUCAGUGAAGGACAGUGGCCUUAGAGCUAUUGAGAAUUUGAUGCAAAAGAAGGGGAAAUUUGAUUACAUACUGUUAGAGACCACUGGAUUAGCAGACCCUGGUGCAGUGGCUUCUAUGUUUUGGGUUGAUGCUGAAUUAGGGAGUGAUAUUUAUCUUGAUGGUAUCAUAACUAUUGUGGAUUCAAAAUAUGGAUUAAAACAUUUAACAGAAGAGAAACCUGAUGGCCUUAUCAAUGAAGCUACUAGACAAGUUGCUUUGGCAGAUGCCAUUCUCAUUAAUAAAACAGACCUGGUUCCAGAAGAAGAUGUAAAGAAAUUAAGAACGACAAUUAGAUCCAUAAAUGGACUAGGACAAAUCUUAGAAACACAAAGAUCAAGAACAAUAAACAUGCAGUGAUUGAUUUUUCUUACUUCAAGUGGAUGAGUGAGCAAGUGACUAAAAUCUUCUGUGAAUUAUUCAGUGUAUGGUGCUUGCCAGUGCAUCUGAGAAUCUAGGGACUUUCUGAAAUAGUACUUCCUUGCUAUGAGGACUGAAGUUGCAUUAGAAUCCUUUUCAAUGAAGAUCAGAUGUCCUGAGUACAAUUCUUACUAUUGGGUCCUGAAUCUUACAUUAAAUAUUCUCUCAAAUUCCUUGAGGCAUAGCAACUUGAGCUUACCAGUUUAGAAACUGGAGAUUUGGGCUGGGCGCGGUGGCUCACGCCUGUAAUCCCAGCACUUUGGGAGGCCAAGGUGGGUGGAUCACGAGGUCAGGAGAUGGAGACCAUCCUGGCUAACACUGUGAAACCCCGUCUCUACUGAAAAUACAAAAAAUUAGCUGAGCCUGGUGGUGGGCGCCUGUAGUCCCAGCUACUCAGGAGGCUGAGGCAGGAGAAUGGCGUGAACCCGGGAGGCGGAGCUUGCAGUGAGCUGAGAUCGCACCACUGCACUCCAGCCUGGGUGACAGAGCGAGACUCUGUCUCAAAAAAAAAAAAAAAAAAAAAAACAAAACCGGAGAUUUGGUUAACAAAAUAGUCAAAGUCACUCUUAUAGAAGUUUUGUUUUAUUUUUUGUUUAAAAUUUUUUUACCAUUUUGUAGCUGACAAGUACUGACAAUAAACUGCUAUAAGCAUGUGUAGAAAAAGGCUCACCUUGAGUAGUUAAGAGUAAGGAAAAGGAAUAGUGUGUAGCAUCGUCUUAGUGGUAAGACUUAAGUUGAUUUAGUAGCAAAUGGAAGUACUAGUGAACCACAUAGAUUUCAGAAGUAGGAGUAAAAGGUUAGAAGAUGUGUCAUUUUAAUCUUCUCUAGACUUUUUCUUAAUUUUUAGAAAUGUAAGUGGACUGAACAGAGGAAAACCAAAACACAGCUGGUCAAUAAUAAGUUAAAUUAAUUUGACAAACUGCCUACUAUGCAUUUCAUAGCAUUUUAAGGACUAUAUAAGCAAUGGAUAAGGCAAAAACUCUGCCUUUAAGGAGAUCAGUCAUUGGGGGGAAACAGAAGCAAACAAACAAAAAGGCAACAUAAUAGAUAUUAAUAUUAAUACAAGAAUUUUAAAAGCACAGAGUUCUAUAAUAAUAGGAAAAUAGAGGGAAUGAUUGCUCAACUUUUCUUGAAAAAGAGUCAGGAAAAUAUUGACCGAGAAGACAGUCAUUGACCUGAGUCUUAAAGAAUGAAUAAGGCUUUUACAGAUGGAGUAGGGUAGGGAUAACUUUCCAGGUAUAAGGAAGAUUUUGUAUUCCAGGGACCUUUGAAUUUUUUAGAAUGGCUAGAAAACUUGGUAUUAUGUAGCACAGAAAAAGUGGUAUGACUGAAGAGAUAGAGAACUUACCACAAAGGGUCUUGAAUGCCAUGAUACAUAGUUUGGAUUUUCUUCUGUAGGGAGCAAGGAGUUAGUGAAGGAUUUUAAAAGCAACAUGCCUCUUGGGAGGUAGAUUCAAUGUGAGGCUAAUCUCCGAGGUAUAGGAAAUACAGGAAGGAGGAGCAACAGGUCGGGUAGUGGUGGAAGCAGGUUUGGAAAAUGUGAUUAGUUUUGUAAGCGUUUUUGAGUUUGAAGUGCCACUGGGGAAGGCUUUUGGAAAUUUAUUUCCAGAGUUCAAGACUGAGCUAUCAUUGCAGUUUGCUCAGCUAUUUACUGAGCUAUCUACUGUCAAUUUGGAUAGUAUCUACAGUUUGCAUUGUAGAUACUGGAUACUUGGAUUGGCUGGUGCACCCUGUUUGUGAGACUCACUGGAGUUUGAAGAGAUGACCACUGGAAAAUAUCCCUAAGCAGUAGCUGCAAUUCCACCCCCACCUUGGAGAGCCAAAACCCUCUUCAUUUUCACUCUCCUGUCCUUGGUCUUAGGCUACUUAAAGCAGCCUUUAGACAUAGGGAAAAAUUGAAAGCCUCUCUUUUAAGAAAAACAUUAGGUACUUCUGGAAUAGAGAGUUCAAGAAAUUAGGAGAAAAAUGAACUUUUGAAGCUUUUUCUUUCCCUUUUUUGUUUACUUCAUUCUCUUACUCAGUUUUAAAAUGCUGGUAAUGGUCUUUUUUUUCUUUUUUUUUUUUUCUUGGCGAUUUUAAUGCUUUGGAAAAGAUCUCAUGGUUUUAUCUCCAAAGGAGGAAAUUAAUUUGAUGCCAUGGAAAUUAGUUUUCUAGUCGUAUGCCUUGAAUGAGUGAAGAAUUUGUUUUUCAUGGUGGUACUAAAUUUGGGGAAAGCUAUAGAAACUUUCAUCUGGAAGCUUACACUUUUCCUCUUUUUUGAAAAUUUGGUGAGAGACUUGGAUAUUUUAUUGUUUUCUGUAAAAGAGUGUAAUUUGUUGUACAGGUCUAAUAUUGAUCCUUUUUUGGAAGUAUGGAAAGAAUCUGAGUAUAAAGCAGAAUUACCUCUGGAUGGCAUGUAUUCUCAAGGACACUGUCACAGUGAAACAGUUUAUUUAGAAGCUUGUGUUUCCAAAGUGUUGAAUUUGAUAUUCACAAAAUUGGCAUGUGUAAACUUUAUUAAACUUUAAGCUAUUUCCUAAGAUGAAGAUGACAAACUUGGAGGGAAACUUCAUUCAUUUGGUUUAUUUUUAUUUUUAUUUUUAUUUAUUUUUAUCUUUUUGAGACAGAAUCUCACUCUGGUUUGAGACAGAAUCUCACUCUGUCCCCCAAGUUGGAGUGCGGUGGUGCGACCUCGGCUCACUGAAACCUCUGCCUCCUGGGUUCAGGCGAUUCUCCUGCUUCACCCUCCGAGUAGCUGGGAUUACAGGUGUGCACCACCACACCCAGCUAAUUUUUGUAUUUUUAGUAGAGACGGUUUCGCCACAUUGGCCCGGUUGGUGUCAAACUCCUGGCCUCAAAGUGAUCCGCCCACCUUGGCCUCCCAAAGUGGAGCCGCCGUGCCCCUUGUCUGUGACCUGUCAAUAUAAAUAUGCUCAGUAGCGGGGGGAGGGGGAGGUGAAAAAGGAAAUAUGUUUAAUAUUAAGACUUUGGCCUUUUAGUGUAAACUGAUACUCAGAAAUUUCUUCAUAGAACAUUUGCUUCUUUGCUUGAUCAUUUUUCUAAUUCUGUACAUCUAAAAUGCCCAGAAUUUGAGUUGCUGUUAUAGUCUACUAACAUAGAACUUUGGAGUAAUAAGAUGGGAAUUUGUCUCUCUUUUGCCAAGACAAGCAUUCGUAAUCUAACACAGUAUUGUUGCCACGAGUACGAGUAUGUGAUAGACUGUUGAGAAUAAAGAAAGCAGGCACAGUUGGUCAGUCCUAAGAUAAAGGAGAUGUUUUUCUUAUAUGUUUGUGCAUUAAAGAAAAAAAAAUCUUGAAUCUGACCAAUGAUGUUUUUUUUCCUUGUAAGAAAAUUUAACAAAUGUUUGGCAAGCUUCUGGAAUCUAAAUUUGAAAUUAUACAUUUGUCAUUUUCUUUAAAUAUUUCUUCACCUUAGCUUUGAUUAUGAGAAAUCACUGUCCUCUGCUGUUCUUUUUUUUUUUUUUUUUCUUUUGAGGCGGAGUCUCACUCUGUGCCAGGCUGGAGUGCAGUGGUGCAAUCUUGGCUCACUGCAACCUCCACUUCCUGGGUUCAAAUGAUUCUCCUGCCGCAGCCUCCUGAGUAGCUGGGACUACAGGUGCGUGCCACCACACCCAGCUAAUUUUUGUAUUUUUGGUAGAGACAGGGUUUCACCACGUUGUCCAUGGCCAGGAUGGUCUUGAUCUUGACCUUGUGAUCCGCCCGCCUCGGCCUCCCAGAGUGCUGGGAUUGCAGGCAUGAGCCACCGCGCCCGGCCUGUCCUCUGUGGUUUUCUGGGCUUAUGUUAAAAUUAUAACUCAAUCACCAGUCUUUAUAAAUUUGCUUUUUUAUAUUUAAACCAAACCUAAUGCUAAUUGUGAUAUGUUAUUUAUUCUCACCUGAUUUGAAUCAUUGGAUUCAAUUAAAUGAGUAAUUAUCAUUAAAUAAUUCUAAGAGAAAUAAUGUCUAUUCGGAUGGUGGGAAUUUUCUUCCUACAUGCAGCCCCAUUCUGAAUGAAUGAAAUCAAAUCACGUGAAGAUCAGGGUCCUAGAGUAACUUAAUAUUUUGUACAUUGGUUAUUUGACUCCUCAUUUUUAUAUUACAUGUUAUAUCAAGGGAGGGGGUAUAAAAGAAAUACAAAAAUUGCAGAGGUAUCUGGAAUGUACCUAUUUGUUAAUUCUAUUUGUCAUUUCUUUUGUUUCAUCUUUUGAGUAAUAAGCUGC